AUCCCAGCACUUUGGGUGGCCGAGGCGGGUGGAUCACCUGAGGUCAGGAGUUUGAGACCAGCCUGACCAACACGGUGAAAUCCCGUCUCUACUAAAAAUACAAAAUUAGCCAGGUGUGGUGGCACAUGCCUGUAAUCCCAGCUACUCGGGAGGCUGAGGCAGGAGAAUCACUUGAACCUGGGAGGCAGAGGUUGUAGUGAGCUGAGAUUGUGCCAUUACACCCGAGCUUGGGCAACAAGAGUGAAACUCUGUCUCAAAAAAAAAAAAAAAAAAAAAAAAAAAAAGCAAAUGGACACAGGGAUGGUGAAUUAGGACUUGAAGGAAAAAAAUGGGAAAAAGAAAACAGAGGCCGGGCGUGGUGGCUGAUGCCUGUAAUCCCAGCACUUUGGGAGGCCGAGGCAGGUGGAUCACUUGAGCUCAGAAGUUCAAGACUACUCUGGGCAACAUGGCAUAACCCCAUCUCUACAAAAAUACAAAAUUUAGCCAAGUGUGGUGGUGCACACCUGUAGGCCCAGCUACUCGGGAGGCUGAGGUGGGAGGACCGCUUGAACCCUGGAGGUAGAGGCUGCAGUGAGCUGUGAUUGUGCCACUGCAUUCCAGCCUGGGCAACAGAGUGAGACCCUGUCUCAAAAAAACAAUUAAAAAAAAAAGCAGCAUAGGUGAUAAAAUCAUGGUGGGGAGAGAGAACCUAUAUAUUGAGUCCUGGCUUGAUGCCUUUGGUGUAUAUGUCUGCCGCCUUUUAAUCUCUUCCCCUCUAGAUUGCUUCCUGAGGAGGCUGGCACUUCUGAAGAUCCUGAAGACCCUAAAGGAGAUUCACAGGCAGCUGCAGUUCUGACCUGGAGAUAGACGAAUUGGAGACACCUUCAGACUCGGAGCAGCUGGACAGUGGACAUGAAUUUGAAUGGGAAGAUGAACUACCCCGGGCAGAGGGUCUGGGCACCAGUGAGACAGCUGAAAGGCUGGGCCGAGGUUGUAUGUGGGAUGUGACUGGAGAAGAUGGACAUCACUGGAGGGUGUUCCGAAUGGGACCACGGGAGCAGCGCGUAGACAUGACUGUCAUUGAGCCCUAUAAGAAAGUCCUGUCUCAUGGAGGUUACCACGGUGAUGGCCUCAAUGCUGUCAUCCUUUUUGCUUCCUGUUAUCUACCCAGAAGCAGCAUCCCCAACUACACCUAUGUCAUGGAACACUUGUUUAGGUAUAUGGUGGGAACUCUGGAGCUGCUAGUAGCUGAAAAUUACCUGCUUGUUCAUUUGAGUGGAGGCACAAGCAGGGCCCAAGUUCCACCUCUAAGCUGGAUACGUCAGUGUUACCGUACCCUGGAUCGGCGGCUACGGAAAAACCUGCGAGCCCUGGUGGUUGUCCAUGCUACAUGGUAUGUGAAAGCAUUUCUGGCACUGCUUCGGCCCUUCAUCAGUUCCAAAUUCACACGAAAAAUCCGUUUUCUGGACAGCCUGGGGGAGCUGGCCCAACUCAUAUCCCUGGAUCAAGUCCACAUCCCUGAAGCUGUCAGACAGCUGGACCGGGAUCUCCAUGGCUCAGGAGGGACAUAGCACAGGACUGGAUAAAAGGCCUUAGAACCAGUUAGUGAUCUGCCUACACCUGAAUCCCUGAAACAUCUGAACUGUUUUGUAAAUCAUCUUAUCCCCAACCUCAGUACCACCGGAUCUUCACUUCUCAGUGGGAUUUUGUCCUUUGCAUGACCCUACUUUCAGCAGGGCUUUGAGGCUGGGAAACUGAUCUGCUGGGUGACUUUCAUUCCAGUUGCUGGGACGGAAGGCUGAAUGUAGGGUCAUUUUGUAUGGGAUAUGCAGAGCUCUGGGUUUUUUUGUUUUUUGUUUUUUGAGACGGAGUCUCGCUCUGUCGCCAGGCUGGAGUGCAGUGGUGCGAUCUCGGCUCACUGCAACCUCCGCCUCCCGGUUCAAGCCAUUCUUCUGCCUCAGCCUCAGCGAGUAGCUGAGACUACCGGCGCACGCCACCACGCCCAGCUAAUUGUUUUGUAUUUUUAGUAGAGACGGGGUUUCACCAUGUUGGCCAGGAUGGUCUCGAUCUCUUGACCUCGUGAUCUGCCCGCCUCGGCCUCCCAAAGUGCCGAGAUUACAGGUGUGAGCCACCGCGCUCGGCCAGAGCUCUGGGUUUUAAUCCUACUUUAGCUGUAGAACCUUGGGCAAAUAACUUCAUCUUUUUGGGUCCUAAUUUUCCUCCUGUCUAACUGGAGGGACUGUGAUCCUUCCACCUUGGAUGGAAGAGGCUUACCUGACAGCCAGCCUGCCUGCUGGGAGCCAGGAGAGUCAGCUCAUUAAAUCUUGAAGAACCGCUGUAUGCCCUUUUUCCUUCUAAGUCAUGUCUGCUGCCUGUGAGCCUGGGAAGGAGUGCUUUCAAAACCUGUAUUUUUGCCCUCUUUAGUAAAUUUAGAACUGUAGAGGCUAAUAAACUGCGAUGAGACAUUUAAGCUCUGCUCCAAAGAAGUGAACGACUCUUUCACCACCCCUUGCAUCCCAAACCUUCGGUUCUGGCAGAGUUCUUGCCGCAGAGGUUCCUUAGGAGCACCCCGCGCGGCCCGCGCGAGCGCGCCUGCGCGUCGAA